ACAGUCAUCCGUGCGCUGCGCGGCAAACCCUGUCGCGAGGGCGCCCCGAGUUGCUGCGGGGCCUGAUCCGGCUCCUUUCCAACAAUACGCGUCUGCAGCCGGCAUUUCUAGAGCUCUCUGCUUCUUCCCGCUGGAGAAACCAGUGUGUGUCGUGUUGGAAUGCUUCGUCUUGCCCUAGAAUUCAGCUUGCGUCUUGUGGUGCGCAGGUGACAGGACCUGCCGAACUCUUGGUACAGACCCCUAAAUCAUGGCAGAACUGUCUUGAUUUCUUUUUUGCCACCUUUCCGUUUUUGUCCUCUAUAGGCAAGCUAUAAAGAUUUAACCCAGUUAAAAACAGGAGGGAGAUUCAGCGGAGAGGAGGCAUGCGAGAUUCUUUGGAAAAAAUUAUAUAAAUGUAGUUCUUGCUAAUAAUUACCUGGGUUGGAUACUUUGACUUACUGUUCAAGUUCCUAAGAAGGGAUUUUACAUUUCUGGGUCUUGUUUUAAAAACUGUUAGAAAGCUCGUGAGGGGGUAGGGACAAGCAGUUUUGGUAAUAGGCGAUGCUGUGGAUAAAACUGUGCGGUAAAAUGCCCAAGCUAGAUUCUUCCUAUGCAAAAUAAGACCCGUUCCAGAACACUUUGACCAUUUCGUGGACUUAGAAUUUAAAGGCGGGUGAGGGCGGGGGGGGAGGAGGAGCGGAUUCUAUCACUCUGCAUCCUCAAGGUCAAAUAUUCUUCCAUCAGUUAUUUUGGAUUGAACCAUUCUUAAAUAGGUCUCAGGAUCUCUAUGUCGCUUCCUUAUGACAGAACCUAUUUCCGAGAGUGUGCCUUUGCAUAUCUAUAGAAGCUCCUUUCACUUAAUAUAUCUUAUAACUCAGAUUCAAUUGCUGUACUUGCUAAAUAAUGCAUUUUUAAUCAUUCAAAAAGUGGUUUACAGCUUCCUUGGGUAUAAUGGUUUUUAUGUAAGCCCGUUACAUCAGUGAAAUGCCAGUUUUUAAACAUUGAAGGGAAGGGAGAAUAUUAUUCUUAUUUAUUUCCAUAGGAAGUAGAAUUCAAAGUGCAGGUGCUUUUUUGUUUGCUUUGGAGAAAAAGUAUAGGUCUUUAACAUGACGUUAACAGAAGUCAAAUCUAAGGAUAAUUAGCUUGUUAUGCAAGUUGCAAACAUUUAAGAAGAUCAGAUGAAUUUUUUUUUUUUUUUUUUUUGAGACGGAGUCUCGCUCUGCCGCCCAGGCUGGAGUCCGCGAUCUCGGCUCACUCACUGCAACCUCCGCCCGCCGGGUACAAGCGAGUCUCCUGCCUCAACCUCCCGAGUAGCUGGGACUACAGGUGCAUGCCACCACCCCCGGCUAAUUUUUUGCAUUUUUAGUAGAGAUGGGGCUUCACCGUGUUAGCCAGGAUGGUCUUUCUCUCCUGACCUCGUGAUCCGCCUGCCUCAGCCUCCCAAAGUGCUGGGAUUACAGGCGUGAGCCACCGCGCCUGGCUGAUUAGAUGGAUUUUUAACACUUCCAGUGGUAAUAUAGGGUAAUGUAGCUAGCCUACUCUGUGCUAUGUUGUACGGUAGCACUCUUCAAAAGAAAUUAGAUUGUUCUUGUUCUUUAUUUUUCAUUGUGUGGAAAAGUGCUGAGCCUGCGCUUUGUCCUUGUUUUUGUAGCAUUUGACUUGGCAGUUAAUGGCUUGUGAGCUAAUUUCCUCAUCUGUAGAAUGGGAAGAUUGAUGACACCUGUUUCACAGAAUAGUUGGGAUGAUCACUUGAGGGAAGACGUGAAAUGUCGUCAAGACUCAAACCCUUUAAAAAUACUCGCCUAGUGCACUGGUGGAGGAAGCGAAUGGAAAUAGAGAAGUCCAAGGGCAGAGCCUGGAAAGCUGGGAAGAGGAGGAGCAGCCAGCGGAGGAGCCAGCGAGGGUGUGGACUGGGUUCUGCCGGAGACUUCCAUUUGGCCUCAAUGUGAAAUUAAAGUAGAAAAUCACAUCUACAUGCAUGUUGCUAUCAGGAUGUUGAUUCAUUAGUCAUGCCUGAAGAGGGAAAGUCUGUUUUAGGUGGCUGACUACCAGCAAAAAUAAAUGCUUAUCCUACAUGUCAAGCAUCUCUACUUUUUACUGGAGUGAAAAUCCCCUCCAGAUACCAACAGAAUAUCAACUGCAGAAAAUGCUUCACAUUUUAAGGAUGUCGGCAACCUAAAUUCAUGUACCCUAUCUGUACAGUUGUUGUGGAUGGUUUGCCAUCUGAAAGCUCCUCAAGUUCUUAUCCAGGCCCUGUGUCUGUUUCUGAAAUGUCUCUGCUUCAUGCUUUGGGUCCAGUGCAGACCUGGCUGGGACAAGAGCUCGAGAAAUGUGGCAUUGAUGCCAUGAUUUACACUCGGUAUGUCCUCAGUCUUCUGCUGCAUGACAGCUAUGACUACGACCUGCAGGAACAGGAGAAUGACAUCUUCCUGGGCUGGGAAAAAGGAGCUUAUAAGAAAUGGGGAAAGAGUAAGAAAAAAUGUUCAGAUCUAACUCUAGAAGAAAUGAAAAAACAGGCUGCUGUCCAGUGUCUUCGAUCUGCUUCUGAUGAAAGCUCUGGUAUCGAGACUUUAGUGGAGGAGCUCUGCUCCAGACUGAAAGACCUUCAGAGUAAGCAAGAAGAGAAGAUUCACAAAAAGUUAGAGGGGUCUCCCUCUCCAGAGGCAGAAUUAUCCCCUCCAGCAAAGGAUCAAGUGGAAAUGUACUAUGAAGCAUUUCCACCACUUUCUGAGAAACCAGUUUGCCUGCAAGAAAUCAUGACUGUGUGGAACAAGUCUAAAGUCUGUUCUUACUCUAGCUCUUCUUCAUCAUCCACAGCCCCACCAGCUAGCACAGAUACUUCCUCUCCUAAGGACUGCAACAGUGAAAGUGAAGUCACCAAGGAAAGAAGCAGUGAAGUACCCACCACUGUGCAUGAGAAAACCCAGAGCAAAAGCAAAAACGAGAAGGAAAACAAAUUUAGUAAUGGCACAAUUGAAGAAAAGCCUGCUUUGUACAAAAAGCAAAUCCGACAUAAACCUGAAGGAAAGAUUCGCCCUCGCUCGUGGUCUUCUGGCUCCAGUGAAGCAGGCUCAAGUUCCAGUGGGAAUCAGGGAGAAUUAAAAGCAUCCAUGAAGUAUGUUAAAGUAAGACACAAGGCACGAGAGAUUCGAAACAAAAAAGGGCGGAAUGGGCAAAGCAGGCUUUCUUUGAAGCACGGUGAAAAGGCUGAAAGGAACAUUCAUACUGGAAGUAGUAGCAGUAGCAGCAGUGGUUCUGUCAAACAGCUGUGCAAGCGGGGUAAGAGACCUUUAAAAGAAAUAGGGAGAAAAGAUCCUGGGAGCACUGAAGGAAAAGACCUGUACAUGGAGAAUAGAAAGGACACAGAGUAUAAAGAGGAGCCCUUGUGGUACACCGAGCCAAUUGCUGAAUAUUUUGUUCCUCUGAGCAGAAAAAGUAAACUAGAGACCACAUACCGAAACAGACAGGAUACAAGUGAUCUGACAUCAGAGGCAGUGGAAGAAUUGUCUGAAUCAGUGCAUGGUCUUUGUAUCAGCAACAAUAAUCUUCAUAAAACAUACCUCGCAGCAGGUACUUUCAUUGAUGGUCAUUUUGUAGAAAUGCCUGCAGUUAUAAAUGAGGAUAUUGACCUCACUGGGACCUCAUUAUGUUCUCUACCAGAGGACAAUAAAUACCUGGAUGAUAUUCAUCUAUCAGAAUUAACGCACUUCUAUGAAGUGGAUAUUGAUCAAUCCAUGUUGGAUCCUGGUGCCUCAGAAACAAUGCAAGGAGAAAGUCGGAUUUUGAAUAUGAUUCGACAGAAAAGCAAAGAGAACACAGAUUUUGAGGCAGAAUGUUGCAUAGUGUUAGAUGGUAUGGAGUUGCAAGGGGAACGUGCAAUAUGGACAGAUUCUACCAGCUCCGUAGGUGCUGAGGGCUUAUUCCUGCAGGACCUUGGCAAUCUGGCUCAGUUUUGGGAGUGCUGUUCAUCCAGCUCCGGUGAUGCUGAUGGGGAGAGUUUUGGAGGAGACUCUCCAGUUAGACUCUCUCCCAUCUUAGACAGCACAGUGCUCAAUUCACACCUGCUUGCUGGCAAUCAAGAGCUCUUUUCAGAUAUUAAUGAAGGAUCUGGUAUAAACUCUUGUUUUUCAGUGUUUGAAGUGCAAUGCAGUAAUUCUGUUUUACCAUUUUCUUUUGAAACACUCAACUUGGGAAAUGAAAAUACAGAUUCUAGUGCUAAUAUGCUUGGGAAAACACAGUCUAGAUUGCUAAUAUGGACCAAAAAUAGUGCCUUUGAAGAAAAUGAACACUGUUCUAAUCUUUCAACAAGAACUUGUAGUCCAUGGUCCCAUUCAGAAGAAACACGUUCAGACAAUGAAACAUUAAAUAUUCAGUUUGAAGAAUCCACACAGUUUAAUGCCGAAGAUAUUAAUUAUGUAGUUCCUAGAGUCUCGUCAAAUUAUGUAGAUGAAGAACUUCUAGAUUUUUUGCAAGAUGAAACUUGCCAGCAAAACAGUAGAACUUUAGGUGAGAUUCCUACAUUAGUUUUCAAAAAAACAUCUAAACUAGAAUCCGUCUGUGGUAUUCAGCUAGAACAAAAAACAGAAAACAAAAAUUUUGAAACUACACAAGUAUGUAAUGAAAGUCCACAUGGAGAUGGCUACAGCUCAGGGGUUAUUAAAGACAUUUGGACAAAGAUGGCAGACACAAAUUCUGUGGCUACAGUAGAAAUAGAAAGAACUGAUGCUGAGUUGUUUUCGGCAGAUGUAAAUAACUACUGCUGCUGUCUAGAUGCUGAAGCUGAACUGGAGACCCUUCAGGAGCCUGAUAAGGCUGUGCGGAGGUCAGAGUACCAUCUGUGGGAGGGACAGAAAGAGAGCCUGGAGAAAAGAGCAUUUGCUUCUAGUGAGCUAUCAAACGUGGAUGGUGGUGAUUAUACAACACCCUCUAAACCCUGGGAUGUAGCCCAAGAUAAAGAAAACACAUUCAUUCUUGGAGGAGUUUAUGGAGAACUCAAAACCUUCAAUAGUGAUGGGGAGUGGGCAGUCGUACCACCUAGUCACACAAAAGGAAGUCUGUUACAGUGUGCAGCUUCUGAUGUUGUGACGAUAGCUGGUACAGAUGUCUUUAUGACCCCAGGAAACAGUUUUGCUCCUGGGCACAGGCAGUUAUGGAAACCCUUCGUGUCAUUUGAACAGAAUGAUCAGCCGAAGAGUGGGGAAAAUGGGUUAAAUAAGGGAUUUUCUUUUAUCUUCCAUGAAGACUUACUAGGAGCUUGUGGCAACUUUCAAGUCGAAGAUCCUGGACUUGAAUACUCAUUUUCUUCCUUUGACUUAAGCAAUCCAUUUUCACAAGUUCUUCAUGUAGAAUGCUCAUUUGAACCUGAAGGGAUUGCAUCUUUCAGCCCCAGUUUUAAACCGAAAUCAAUCCUCUGUUCUGAUUCAGACAGUGAAGUGUUUCACCCCAGGAUAUGUGGUGUUGACAGAACACAAUACAGGGCUAUUCGGAUCUCUCCUCGGACUCACUUUCGCCCAAUUUCUGCAUCCGAACUGUCCCCAGGAGGAGGAAGCGAGUCAGAAUUUGAAUCUGAGAAAGAUGAAGCAAAUAUUCCCAUUCCUUCUCAAGUUGAUAUAUUUGAAGAUCCGCAGGCAGAUCUCAAACCUUUGGAAGAAGAUGCAGAGAAAGAAGGCCAUUACUAUGGAAAAUCAGAGCUUGAGUCUGGAAAAUUCCUUCCCAGGUUAAAAAAAUCUGGGAUGGAAAAGAGUGCUCAGACAUCACUGGAUUCCCAGGAGGAAUCAACUGGGAUUCUUUCAGUAGGAAAGCAAAAUCAGUGUUUGGAAUGUAGCAUGAAUGAAUCCCUGGAAAUAGAUUUAGAAAGCUCAGAAGCAAAUUGUAAAAUAAUGGCACAAUGCGAGGAAGAAAUUAAUAAUUUUUGUGGUUGCAAAGCAGGUUGUCAGUUUCCUGCUUAUGAAGAUAAUCCAGUUUCUUCGGGACAGCUGGAAGAGAUUGGGAAGAAAGAAAAAGAGGAAAGAAGCAAGAUUCUACAUCAUACCACUACCAUAUUCCUUCGCUUUCUAUUCCCUGUAUUGAACACUGAUAUACAAGGAAUGAAUAGAAGUCAAGAAAAACAGACCUGGUGGGAAAAAGCCUUGUACUCUCCUCUUUUUCCUGCAUCAGAGUGUGAAGAAUGUUACACAAAUGCCAAGGGAGAGAGUGGUUUAGAAGAAUAUCCAGAUGCUAAAGAGACACCCAGUAAUGAAGAGCGCCUGUUAGAUUUUAAUAGGGUGUCUUCUGUUUAUGAAGCAAGAUGUACAGGAGAGAGAGAUUCUGGAGCAAAGUCAGAUGGCUUCCGCGGAAAGAUGUGCUCCAGCGCCAGCUCCACCUCGGAAGAGACAGGCUCAGAAGGCGGAGGCGAGUGGGUGGGCCCUAGUGAAGAGGAGCUCUUUUCUCGAACUCAUCUCUAAACCUGCAAAAUAGUACAAAUUAUUGUUUAAAAAUGAUAUGUGAUGGAAAAUUACUCUUCAGUGAGACCUGUUAAUCUAAAACAACAACUUAGGUUUCCUCUUCAAUUAACUGAUUCAGAUUGGUAAUAAUUAUCUUUCUCUUCUUGCUUAUUUUAGAGUUGAGGACAGCUAUCCUGUUAAAGAUUUUUUUUCCCAGCUGUUAAAUUCUUGGCUAUUUGAAAUAGACUAGAUUGUGUUGUCAAAUCAAGAAUGGGUGUGCAUGUGCUUGUCUUAGAAGUAUCACUGCUUUUUGCAUCUUAACUGCAGUUAAUUUUCCUUCCGACUGCGGUUAUAUCACUAUGACCUUACUAGCAUUGCAGUGUCAACAACCACUUCUGCUCUUCAGAGACUUCAGCUUUGGAGCAUUUAGGCUUUGUUCUCCAAGAACUGGGAUAUCCAUUCUUACCCUACAGUGGCUUGAUGCCUUUCUGAAGGCGAGAGGGAAGCCUGGGUGACUCAGCGGUGGUCUCCAUUCAGCAAAAUCUCAUGUACAUUUCCAGUAGGAACCGCAGAGGUGUGCUUUUCAAGACUCACCAAAUACUGUGUUUUCUCUCUUAGGAUUUCUUUUCCCCUAAAGUAUCACGGAAGAUACUAUGGUUCGUGACUUUCUUGCUAACUGAAGAAGCCAAGGAUUUGGGGUGUGGGGUCGUAUGCGAGACACAGUGGGGUAAGGGUGCAUACCCCACCCCUUACCUGCUCUCAUACUGCAGUUACAUUUACACCAAAACCCCAUGCAGGGUUCUUUGUGGUGAGUGUUCCAUACGUGCUAAGGACCUUAGUUACAGAUUGUUACUUUCUGGUGACCUAUGUUGAAUUGAAACCCCCAAAACUUGAAAUUGUGAACAUUUGACAUGCAGUAAAGGCCACCUCAUCACCCAGAGAAAUCUUUGGCUGCUGCAGCUAGCCGCUUCUUGGCUGUGAUGUAGUAUAGCUUCGAUCUCAUUUUGUGUUUGAGAGAAUGUUCUGGGCAAGUUCUGUGUGUGGUGGGUUGGGGCGGGUAGAGUCAUGAGUUUUCCACAUCCCUGUGUGGUGGUUUUGCUGACUGUCGCUCCGUGGGACUGGCUCCCGUUUCUCCUUGGUGAGCCCGGGGAGCCGGCGCAUCUUGUGAGUCGCGUCUGUGCAUGGCGAUCCGCUCCUCCGGCUCUCAUGGCAUUGUGCCACAGGCAGAGGCCAGGAGGAGCAGUAUGUGCACAGCCGAAACAUUUUACAUUUUUUACAUUGUUUUUCUUUUUUAACCAACUCAUUGUUUAAAAAACAAAAACAAAAAAAACCUAAUCUGUGAAAUCAGCGUAGCAUGCCUGGAGCAUCAGGAAUGGCAGAAAAGUCUGAUGCGCUCUAGACAGCUUCACCACUCAUUUGGGCAGGCAGUAAACACACAUAUAAUUUAUUAGCUGGGAGCUGAACUGGCUGUGAAAUCUAUGAUUUGCUUUGAACAUUUGGGUUUUGUUGCCUUUUUCUUAAUUGAUAACACAGAAAAGAAAGUACCAUCAAAGACUGUGGAGUCAUUGAGGGUCUGUGUGUCCUCACCGAGAGGGACCUGGUGUGCCCGCCGGGUCGAUCUUCCCACGUGUUAGGGUUUAUUUUUAUACAACACAUUUUUUGACACUUUAAGGUGGGUGGGUGUGUGUGUGUGUGUGUGUGUGCGCGCGUGCGCGCGCGCAUGUGUAAGGUUUUAUGUUGCUGUUAUUUAUUUACGAACUUCAGAUACGUUUUUAUGUAUUUUUCAUUCUUCUGGAGCUUCCUAAAAAUUGAUAAGCAUCUGCACUGAAAUAUAAUUUAACAGCAAAAGUAAAAAAGGAUUGAAAGUUGUAAAUUCCUCAUAUCACUACAGUGACGAUUAUUCUAGAAAUCGUUGCUUGUGUAGCAAAGACCAAAUAAAUAGAUUUCAGACACAACCUUGAGCACAGUUGAUUUUGGACAGCUGCUGUUUAUUAGGAAAGGGCUCCAGGUGGCAAAGGUGCACACUUCCUCAGACACAGGUGAGAAGAUGCAGCACCUUCCACAGGUGAAUGGGACGGAUUCGAAGUGAGCAAAGGGAUUCACAAAUUAUGUAUUUAUUUGUUUUCAUAGUUAAGUAGCUGAAGCUCAGAGGCUUUCAGCAACAGAGAUGAAAGUGUGGCUUUUUAGUUUUGUGAAUGGAUGAUCACAAAGAAAAAGCAUUUUUAAAAAGUUGGCAAACGCUGAAACGCACUGUGGUAUGAAGCGCAUUGCAUUUCCAUAGCACUGAAGUACCAGUUUCCAUUCCUGGGCUGAGAUUGUUUUUCCCGUGGUUGUAUUGUUCUGAUUUCACGUACACCAGAGUAACUGAUUUUUUUUUGUUUGUUUUCUUGUGGAGUUAACACCAAAUAAAAAUUGUAAAAAACAGUUUGUUGUUUUUAUUUCUCAUAGCAAAGCUUCUUUUGUAAAGAACUCCAGCUUCCUUUUACUCAUGAGCAUCCGUGGAAGAGCAAGUGCCCAGGUUACAUUUGUUCUAGAUGGAGGUCAUUUAGCUCUCAUUGCAGACACUGCUGAAAACAUUGUGCAGCUUUGCUAGGGAAGAAAGUGGUGUGGCCUGCUGAGAAAUCAGCGGCUCCUCCCCAUCUCACCCCCAGCACACGCAGGGACUACUACCUGAGUCUGCAAAACACAUAGCAUUUUUGUCCGUGGAUGGUACACAAAGCUCAAUCUUUUUGUUUUCUUCUGGGGAAAAAAUUAAAUCUUUAUAUGUUAAUAUGAUUGAUAUUCAUUGUGCAAAAAAAAUCAGUGUGUUUUUAAAGAAGUAUAAGGGAAAAGGAAAACUCAUAUGUCCUUCUGUCACUCUGAGACAUACACUGGUAACAUCUGUGCAAGCCCCUUUCCAGGAUUCUGAAUGUACAGUAUAUAUGAAUGCAUACACAGAGAAAUUUACAUUCAAGAGUGUACUAUACUUGUUCUUCUAUAACAUCAGAAAUAGGUUUUUACUCAGAUGUCUUCAUGUCGGUAAUUAUAGAACUACAUAAUUAUUUUUAUAGCUGUAUUAUGUAGAUUUAACAGGUUCCUCAUUGAUAAAACAAUGUUUUUUUGGUUGUUUAUUCAGUAUCUGAAUAACGUUUCUAUGGACAUCUGUAAACAUGUAUGAGGGGACUUUUAAAAGUUCAUGGAAAAUGGAAUUAAAAGAAAAAUAAAAAAAUAUAAACUUUA